UCCACCUAUCUGUGGUGGCAACCCCUUGAGGUCAAGACCCCACAAUCAGAUGAGGAUGGAGUGGCUCACCCUCAGUCAACAGGCCAGACUCAAGGGGUUCCAGGCAAGUCAGUUCUCCCUCAGGCCUUCGGUUUCCUCACCCACAAGAUGAGAGGGCUGGACCAGAUGGAAAUUCAGGGGGUAAGGGGAUGUCCGCUCGCAGCCCACCUCGCCCAUGGGCCCCUCAAGCCUCCCUGCCAGUUCCCACGACGCACCCGCCCCACAGAUCCUGCCCAAGGUGAGGGCUGGUCCCGGGUCCUCCGGCUGCCGCAUCAGCGAGUGCAGGAGGGAGGGGAAGCCUCCAACGGGGCGACUGGGGCUCAAGGAUGCAACUCGGCCAGGAGUGAACUUGGGCACGGAGGGAGGUGUCUGGGCCGCUCCUCGAGCCCAGCCUGGGUCCACGACCCCCUUACCUCCAGGGUCCGUAUCUCCUGCUGGGUGAGGUCCUUGGACACAGCGCACUUGUUGCGCAACCGGCGCAGGCUGCCAAUGGAGAUGCGGAUAAGCUUCUGGAGCUGCCCACAAGCUUCUGGAGCUGCCCACACUGCUGCAGCGUCUGGCUGGCUGCGGCCCCUGCGCCUCCCAAAGAGGCCGCCACAUCACCCCCGCCACCGCCCUCCUUCUUCUCUCCCCUGGCCGCUACGCGCAGCGCCGCUCUAUGCAGGCCGCAGCGGCCAAGGCGGGGAGCCCGGGGCGCGGGCGCCUAGGCAAGGAACCCCCGAGCCGGGAGAGCUGGACCAGGAGCGCCCCCCGGCGCCGCCUGAACAAGGACGCCGAGCCGCGGCAGCGGUGGCAAAAAGCGGCGGCGGCGGGGGCAAAAAGCUGGGGCGGCGGGGACAAAAAGCCUCGGUGGCGGGGGCAAAAAGCCACGGCGGCAAAAACCGGCGGCGGCGGGAGCAAAAUGCCGCAGGGGCAAAAAGCCGCAAAAAGCCGCGGCGGCGGGGGCAAGAAGCCGCGGUGGCGGGAGCAAAAAUCUGCGGCGGCAAAAAGGGGCGGCGGCGGGGGCAAAAAGCCGCAAAAAGCCUCGGCGUCGGGGGCAAAAAUAUGCGGCGGCGGGGGCUGGAGCCCAUGCGAGGGUCUGCAGUCUUUGUUCCGGAUGGGGAACUACUGCUUCAGCUGGUUACCCAGGUGCCCCGAUGGGGAAAGGAAGGAAAUGGUGAGAAUCUUCAGCACAGCGGAUCACAUCACCCUGGAAGAGACCAGUCCUGCCUGCGCAUAGCACAAGCAGCCGCAGGCUAG